CCCUCGGGCUGCCCUUCCAGCCAGGCGUCCAUCUUAAGAGACGCUGGUCUCCUCAGGCGUGAAGAUUGGAUUUGGGUUGGGACUGGGAAGUCUCGCUAAAGGGUGAAUCAUGUUUAAGAAGGUCAACAGGAUUGAGCACAAGAGGAAUAAGACAGAAAAACCAAAAAAGCUUAAUCCAUGGAUUCCACGCAUCUUCAACCACAAAUGCUUUGUCACCUUCCUUACUGGCUGCUAUAGUUGCCUCUGGAAAUUCAGACAAUGGGAAAAAACUAAAGUUGGAUUUUGUUGCUGCACUUGGGUACAGACUGAUAAGGAGCUGGACCACAUUUUCUCAGAUGCGGGGAGCAUAGGCUGACUGCUGGGCCCCAUGAGGGCUCUUUAUGGUCUCCAGGACUGGGGAUGCUAGGGCUCCAUUUCUUCCAUAAAAGUAUUGCACCAAUGUUAAACUUACUGAAACAUGUACUUGCUUUCUUCAUUUUCUUUCCUUCACUUCAUUUUUCACUUUUAUUCUUUACUUUUCCUUACUACCUCUUUUAUGUUUAUUCAUUAAUUCACUUUUGCAUUUAUUCAUUCAGUGAAUCUUGAAGAAAAAGUGAUGUUUGGGUGCAAUUAGAUAUUUUUGGUUACGGAUUACAGGGAUGCCUGAAUUGUAAUUUGCUCUCCUCUGUGAAUUUCUCUUCGCAGGAGAAAAAAACAGCAAGUGAGAAACAAGGUGCUCCUUUAUUAUUGGUCAAGCUAGUGGUGAUUUUCCCUGAGGAAGAACUCUAGUAAGGCUGAGUGGUGGCACGUGGACUAGCCUUUUUUAGGGCCUCUAUUUGUAAGCCAUAUGUUGGAACCCUUUGGUGAGCUACAUGGUAUAAGUGAUUAAAUGAUCAGCACACUGAAAUGAGAACAGAAGAGCAAAAUCAUGUACCUUUACUUAUUUGUAAACAUGGUCCAACUAGGGUCCCAGAAUCAGACCAGUUGGGUCAUUAAUUUCUUAUACCUGAGGUGGGGAACACAAGGAAAGGGGUAGGAAAUGGGAGGUUUCCCUGCAGUAGGAAGGAAUGUUCUUCUGUCCCCACUGUAUCUUUCCUGCCCAGAUAUUCGGCCUCUAUGCUAGUCACUGGGGAUAAUACAAGUGCUUCAGGCAUGGUUCCUGCUCUCAAGGAAUUCAGUCUACUGUGGGGAAAGAUAAGUACACACACAAUCUCAAUAUAGUGAGAGAAGUGCUGUAACUGUAUGCGCAUGUACACAGGCACAUACCAAGGGGAGGGCCACCUUUUAGAAGGUGAUGGGUGAUUAAGAAUUGGAUAGGUAGAGAAUUGGGGAUGGUGGAAGAAUUGGUAUUGGAGGAGUAGUCAAAGGGCAUAAUGAGUUUGGAGACUGAUACAAGGUUUAUUUUAGAUGAAGGAGAGGAUAUGAAUGUGAAGAAGUGAGGGGAAAAGAAGCUAGAGAGGGAGAUGGGUCCAAUGUUGUGUGGUUUUAAGAAUUUGACUUCUGCCAUGUUGGGAAUAAAGAAUCCCCAAAGACUUUAAGCUGAUGAAGUAGUCUGAGCUGUGUUUUGGAAUGAUUAUUUGAUUGUGUGGAGGACGUAUUGAAAAGGACAAAACUAACACAGGGAGACUUCUUUGCCUUCAGAGAAAGCAGUACCUUCUCCAUAAUGAUAACCUCCAUUUUGGCUUUGAGCUUACACAGAUCUGGGUUCUAGUCCUGCCCCUGCCACUUCUUAGCUGUGUGAUCUUGAAUCAAUUAUUUUACCUCUCUGAGCUUUCUUCUGCAAAAAUGAGGUUGAUGCCCAACUCAUAUGGCUCUAAUGAGAAAUAAAUCAAAUGAAAGUAGCUUGUGAAAUUCCCUAGCAUUUUACUAGAACAAAAUAGCUACUUAAAAAAAAUUAUUCUUUAACUCUGAUUCCCCCUUUCUUCUCCAAUGGGGUAGAUUGAUGACUAAAUGAACCAAUUAAUGAUGAAUGAAUCAAUAAAUUAAUUGCUGAACAAAACAUUUGAUAGCUGGAGAGGCAGAUGAAUUCAACAGAUGAUUGUUGAGAGCCAGCUGCAUUCAAGAAACAAUGCUAUGUAUUGGUAAUACAGAGACGUUCCUUUUCCUCAAAGAAGAAACAGUGUAGCAUCAGAUAAAACAUAAAUGCAUAAUUCCAGUUAAGUGUAAGAAAGGUUGUAAAUAGGCAUAUACAGGAUUUGGUAGGGGUAAAAAGAAGAGAGUGAUCACUCCAGCCUCAGGAGGGUAAUGCAUGGCAGUGCAACUAUGCUGACCUUUGGCAAGUGUAUACAGAAACUGCUGAGGUAACAAGGAUAAAUGGAGCUAAGUUAGAUUUCUUUUUUCUUUUCCCAGAAAGAGCAAUUAUUUUGCCGUGCCUGGUAAUUUCAUUUGUCUUGUCUCUGAUGUUGCUGUUCCUGUGGAUAGAAACAUCCAGUGAAUACUUUAACUUUGACUGUUACUUGGAUUUUUGUUGCUUUGGGAAAGGAUUGAACUAUACCUGCACUUGUGUCAUAAGAUCCUGAUUCUGCUAGUGAUUCUUCUGUGUGUCAUUUUAAUGUUCAUUAUAUGCAAAUUCUGGAAAGAAAGGUGGCUGGUAGCUGGGCUGUCAAUGCAGAUCUUUGCUCCCUACGUGCACCUGGUCAGCAUAACUGUGAUGGUUAUCCUUUUCUGGCCUGUGGCCUUCUACGUGGCAUGUUUGGAAAGAGAAGUUAGAAUGAGAAGAUACAGGAUGACACAUUCUGAGAAAAAAAGACUCAAGCAAUGUAAUGUAAUCACAAGGUUAAGAGGUCUCUAUUUGAUGCCACUGGGGAUUUAUUCUCCCUGCAUUCAGGAGAAGGAGAAUUUGGGGCCCAAGCCAACCAUCUUUGGACAUAGAGGUGCACCCAUGUUGGGGCCUGAGAAUACCAUGAUGUCCUUUGAGAAAGCUGUUGAACAUGGAGCCCAUGGAUUGGAGACUGAUAUACACUUAAGUUAUGAUCAUGUGCCUUUCCUCAUGCAUGACUUUGACCUGAAAAGAACAACCAAUAUUGGGGAAGUUCAGCCAGAAUCUGCCUGCGAGAACCCUGCCUUCUUCAACUGGGAUUUCCUAUCGACUCUGAAUGCAGGCAAAUGGUUUGUAAAACCAGAGCUCAGGCCAUUUUACAAUAUGAAACCUCUAUCAGAGGCAGAUAAAGAAAGAGCAAGAAAUCAGUCAAUUCCAACACUAGCUGAUUUAUUGACACUUGCAGAGAAGGAAAGAAAAUUUGUGAUAUUUGAUCUUCAUCGCCCUCCACCAAAACAUCCUCUCAGACACACAUUUGUCCGCCAAGUAGUAAGCGUGAUCCUUGCCUCUAAAAUCGAGCAACAUCUGACACCAAAGUUCUAUGUGUUCAUGUGGCUCCUUGCAGAUAUCAUUUCUGUGCUUUUUAUUGUUGCCAUAUUUUGUUUUCACUGGCGGAGAGAGACUGAAAAAGAAAAAUUGUUUGAAACCUCCAGCACUCGCACAGAUACUCAGAGUGGAAGUAAGAAUGAGGAAGAUAGAUAGAUAGAUAGAUUUGCACAUAGCCAUGAAACCUCCUGUCCGAGUUGUGGAAGGUCCUUGGACUCUAGCAGCCCUCUACCCGGCUCUACCCAAGAGUGGAAAGGAACACCAAGGCCAUUUCAAUUUUGCAGCACCAUCCAAGAAACUACUACCUAUCAAGAAUGCUGUCACACCUUUGAAGCCUGGCAAGCAUGAGAUUCAACCACCGAUGCCCACCGUGGUCUUUGAACUCACCCAAGCACCCACCAGGCAGGCUACAAGUGAGGCUACCUUUCAAACUACAUUGCCCACCCUGAAGGUGGAUAAGCCAACCAUGCCCUCCAUAGAGGUCCCCUAUCCUUAAAUAAGAGACCUCUAAGAGAUCCCCAUGGCUGAAUACUCCAAAUAAUCCUAUGUCACAAUAUAUUCCAUUGCAUCUG